AGCGAGGGCGAGCCUACUGGAGUUUGCCGGGGGUGGGAAGAAGGUGGGCCUCGAGCAAAGCCGCUAGAGGUGGGGUGCGGGUGGUCGGCCUCAGGCGAGCCCCGGGGCACAGCCCGGGGCGGGAGGCGGAGCUUGGCGGCCGAGAUCUCCGCGCUGCAGUUAGCCCCGCCGAGCGCCAGGAGCUGCGGACUGCCACUCUCCGCCCCUACCUGAGUGCCGUGCGGGCCACAUUGCAGGCUGCCCUCUGCCUGGAGAACUUCUCCUCCCAGGUUGUGGAACGACACAACAAGCCGGAAGUGGAAGUCAGGAGUAGCAAAGAGCUCCUGUUACAACCUGUGACCAUCAGCAGGAAUGAGAAGGAAAAGGUUCUGAUUGAGGGCUCCAUCAACUCUGUCCGGGUCAGCAUUGCUGUGAAACAGGCUGAUGAGAUCGAGAAGAUUUUGUGCCACAAGUUCAUGCGCUUCAUGAUGAUGCGAGCAGAGAACUUCUUUAUCCUUCGAAGGAAGCCUGUGGAGGGGUAUGAUAUCAGCUUUCUGAUCACCAACUUCCACACAGAGCAGAUGUACAAACACAAGUUGGUGGACUUUGUGAUCCACUUCAUGGAGGAGAUUGACAAGGAGAUCAGUGAGAUGAAGCUGUCAGUCAAUGCCCGUGCCCGCAUUGUGGCUGAAGAGUUCCUUAAGAAUUUUUAAACCAUCUGGCUGGAUCUCGUGGCCUUCCCCCUCAGACUACCCAUGUCUCCACGAAGGCGUCCUGGAGUCACUCCCCGAGCAGCGCGGCGGCGGCAGGGAGUUGGGUUGGGGUGGGCAUUUGAUGCGGGAGGUGGGUGGUGUGCUUGCUAGCUGGGCAAGAAAGCAGCAGUGGACCUGCCCCAAGGCCACACGUGCCUGGUCAGGCUGGCUUCUGAUGUUCAGUCCCCUGGGCCGGGACAGAUUUUUUUUAACGUCUUGAAACUUAAACUCUGUGCUUGUAGGAUACUGUAACCUUUUUGUCUUUUUUUUUUUUUUUUUUUUUAAACCUCCACCUCCAGUGGCUGUGACUGGUCCCAGUGAUUAUACGUUAUUGGUUGCUGUGGGUCUGGGCGGGCCUGGAGCCAGAAGGCGACUUAUUUUUUCUCUCCUAUGCCACCCCAGGUGGGGAGGGAGGGAGGUUUCAGACUCCAGUUUCUCCCUUGCCCUUUUAUUCCCAAGCCUCCUUGGCCCCAGUAUAAGUGUUGGGAACUCUCUGCCAGCUUCCUGAGUUCUGCCUAAAGAUGGCCCCCCAGCACUGGUUGGGGACAAGGGCCAAAUUGGUGACCACCAGUCAUGCCUAGGACCUGGGGCCCAAAAGCCGGGCAACCUCUGGCUACAGGGGCCAUUGGGUGCCCUCCCAGUUGAGAGGGGCCGCUGUUUCGCCUUGUCCGUCAGUGCCAGUGCCUGUGCCAGAGGUGGCGAGGUGAGUCCUCCAGAGCUUCCUGGCCGGGCCCUCCUCCUGCCUGUUCUGGCUCCUCUGCUCCCACGCUAGCUGUCCCUUUUCUGAUUCUGGUGGAUCCUCCCUCCCCUAAUUAAAGUCUCUUUUUGCCCCUUUGGGGCUGCAUGA